AGCAGUGAGAGCGGUUGCGCAGUGAAGGCUAGACCCGGUUUACUGGAAUUGCUCUGGCGAUCGAGGGAUCCUAGUACACCGCAAUCAUGUCUAUUAUGUCCUAUAACGGAGGGGCCGUCAUGGCCAUGAAGGGGAAGAACUGUGUGGCCAUCGCUGCAGACAGGCGCUUCGGGAUCCAGGCCCAGAUGGUGACCACGGACUUCCAGAAGAUCUUUCCCAUGGGUGACCGGCUGUACAUCGGUCUGGCCGGGCUCGCCACUGACGUCCAGACAGUUGCCCAGCGCCUCAAGUUCCGGCUGAACCUGUAUGAGUUGAAGGAAGGUCGGCAGAUCAAACCUUAUACCCUCAUGAGCAUGGUGGCCAACCUCUUGUAUGAGAAACGGUUUGGCCCUUACUACACUGAGCCAGUCAUUGCCGGGUUGGACCCGAAGACCUUUAAGCCCUUCAUUUGCUCUCUAGACCUCAUCGGCUGCCCCAUGGUGACUGAUGACUUUGUGGUCAGUGGCACCUGCGCCGAACAAAUGUACGGAAUGUGUGAGUCCCUCUGGGAGCCCAACAUGGAUCCGGAUCACCUGUUUGAAACCAUCUCCCAAGCCAUGCUGAAUGCUGUGGACCGGGAUGCAGUGUCAGGCAUGGGAGUCAUUGUCCACAUCAUCGAGAAGGACAAAAUCACCACCAGGACACUGAAGGCCCGAAUGGACUAACCCUGUUCCCAGAGCCCACUUUUUUUUCUUUUUUUGAAAUAAAAUAGCCUGUCUUUCA